AGGGAGGAAAGUGAGGAUUCCCUGCCAAAAUGCCUGAGGGCUUCCCUGCCUACCACAGCCCUCUGUGUUCUUAAAUCCUCCUGUCUGAACAGAGGCCAGACUCUGGUUUCCCCCACAGCCUGUCUGUGUCUGUCCUCUGCAAAGCCAUGUGGCUCUACCUGGCGGUUUUCGUGGGCCUGUACUACCUUCUGCACUGGUACCGGGAGAGGCAGGUGCUGAGCCACCUGAGAGAUAAGUAUGUGUUCAUCACGGGCUGUGACUCUGGCUUCGGGAAACUGCUGGCCAGACAGCUGGAUGCACGAGGCUUGCGGGUGCUGGCUGCAUGUCUGACGGAGAAAGGAGCCGAGCAGCUGAGGGGCCAGACUUCAGACAGGCUGGAGACGGUGACCCUGGAUGUUACCAAGACAGAGAGCGUUGCUGCAGCCGCCCAGUGGGUGAAGGAGUGCGUGAGAGACAAAGGACUCUGGGGCCUGGUGAAUAAUGCUGGCAUCUCCUUGCCCACGGCUCCCAAUGAGUUGCUCACCAAGCAGGACUUCGUGACCAUACUGGACGUGAACUUGUUGGGGGUGAUUGAUGUGACUCUGAGCCUGCUGCCCUUAGUGAGGAGGGCCAGGGGCCGUGUGGUCAACGUCUCCAGUGUCAUGGGCCGGGUGUCACUUUUUGGUGGAGGCUACUGCAUCUCCAAGUAUGGCGUGGAAGCCUUCUCUGACUCCCUCAGGAGGGAACUCUCCUACUUUGGGGUGAAGGUGGCUAUGAUUGAACCUGGCUAUUUCAAGACUGCUGUGACCAGUAAGGAGAGAUUCUUAAAGAGCUUCCUGGAGAUUUGGGACCGGUCCAGUCCAGAGGUCAAGGAGGCCUAUGGCGAGAAGUUUGUUGCAGACUAUAAGAAAUCAGCUGAACAAAUGGAGCAGAAGUGCACACAGGAUCUGUCGUUGGUGACCAACUGCAUGGAGCAUGCGCUGAUUGCCUGCCACCCCCGUACUCGCUACUCAGCUGGCUGGGAUGCCAAGCUUCUCUACCUCCCCAUGAGCUACAUGCCCACCUUCCUGGUGGAUGCCAUUAUGUACUGGGUCUCUCCAAGCCCGGCCAAGGCUCUAUGAAGCUAAGGUUGGAUGCAUGGUUGCAUGGAUUUGGGGUGUGCUAUGAGGGGUGGUGUAUCCUUGGGAGAGAUAUAAAGUGGAGGGAGGGAGCCGUCCGGUCAGUAGGGCACCAAUCCCACCUCCUUCAUUACCUCCUGGCCAUGAUUCUCCUGGGAGAUAAUUCUGCUCUCUGGAGAUGUUGGUAGGAAAGUUUCAAGUUACGCAGCUGAGAAACAGGGACCAAAUAGUGCUCCUGGGUGCAUUGUCACCGUGGGUGGCCACUCAAGGGUCCAAGCCUCUAGGGCCAUCCUUGGGCUAACAACUGGGGUGGGUGUGAGCAGGUGGAAGGAGCCUCAGCCCAUGCCAUUACCUCCUGCUUCCUUAUCAGGCUGUGUGUUAAUUCUGGGCCAGUCUACACCCUCCCACGGGGUGGAAAUGGCCUGGAGGAUGUGAGGGCACCCCUCCUCUGAAGAUCCCUGUACACGUGGUGUUGGGACUGGAACCAUUAUGCGGCCCCAUAGGCCUCAGGAGUCAUCCCAGAAGCAGUGGCUGGGAGGUGGUGUCCUAAGUAAGGAUCUGUGCAGAGGACAAAUAAAUCAGUUUUUGAUUUGUCUUGAAA